GGAGAGGGAGAGCGCCUGGGCAAAGCUCAGAGGCUGGGGGUGCGGAACUCAAAACCGACUGCGGAGAGCCCAGCGGGCGGGAGCUGGGGCGCACGUUGGGGCCCUGCCGAGGGGCGGGCAGGGCCCGGUGCCAGCCCCGGCACCGACGGGACGCCCUCCUCCCUCCGCAGGGCGGGAGGAUGCCGCCGCCAGCGAAGGAGGGCGGGCGCAAGGGCCCGCGGGAGCGAAGCGGGAAGAGCGCGCCAGGCACGGCGCAGGGUGAGGAGCGUGCCAAGGGGGCGCCCGCGACAGAGCCCCCCAAGCCGGGCUGGGCCCUGACGCCGCAGGGACUGGCGGCCAUGCUCCCUGCGCAGCGCCACCGCCAUCUGCUCUUCGGCGACCUGCUGGAGGACGUGGGCGCGGCGGCCUCCACCUUCCCGUGCGGGUCGGUGGAACCGGGGUACCGCAUGCCCGACCCGCGCCCGUGGACGCAGUCGCUCGAGCUGCCCGCCGAGCGCCAGAACCGGCUCCUCGGCGUCCUCAAGGCAGCGGAGGCCCGCGGGCGAGUCCGCGCCCUGCGGCUGCGCUACACCCGCAUGCGGGCCGAGGAGAUCGCGCUGCUCAUCCAGCGGCAGAAGUCCGCGCGCGCCGCCAUCCGGCUGGAGCUGUUCCUGCCGCCGCAGCUGAAGCCCGCGCGGAUCCCGGACCCCCUGGACCGCCAAGAGGUGCAGACAAGCCCCGGUAGGGGCGGGGAAAGGGGAGGGGCCCUGCCCGCCUCCGCACACGCCGGACCCCAGCCUCUCUCCCCGGCAGCGGAGGCGCGUGGAGACCAUCCUGGAGGAGAACGUGGAUGGCACCAUCUUCCCGCGGUGACGGCGACUGAGAGUGUGCGACGCGCCCCAGCCUCCCACAUAAAGUUAUAAUUCUCCGAA